CUUUUCAAAAUGGGGUUGACUGGAGGCGGAGGUUGCAGUGAGCCGAGAUCGCCCCACUGCACUCCAGCCUGGUGACUCCGUCUCAAAAAAAAGGGGAGGGGGGCGGGGGAGAGUUGAAAGCUUAAUAUGUACUUUGGGGGCUAUUAAAGCAAACAUUUCGACUAAAGGGGCGAAUCCUCGAAUUGUGCGAUCAAGCACCCGAGAGGAGAGUUGGGGGGGGUCAGGAGGGGUGGGGGCUCCAGGGAAAGCCCGGGGGUCUGGGCCGGGGUCUCGCGGGGCCCUUCCGGAAGGAUCGCGGCCCCCGAAGGUGGGCGUCCCGCGGGGCUCCAGUCUCCAGGACGUUCCGGGAGGCUCCGCGCUCUGGGAGGCCGGCUGCGUGGGGUCCCCGCGCUGCAGCCGCAGAGGCCCCCCAGGGCCGCGGUUCCCGGAGCGGGAAAGUCCCGCGCGGGGGCGGUGGCCUCGGGGGCGGGACGGGGCGGGGGCGGGGGCGCGGGCGGCCGAGCCGAAUCCCCUCCACCGGGACGCCCCGCUGCUGCUCGGGAAGAGGCGGGCCCUGCGCGCCCUGCGCUCGCCAUGGCGGUUUGGGCGGCGACGUGAGCGGCUCCGCGGACCCCGAGCGGGGCCCCGGCCGCGACCUGAGCCGCCGCCGAGCGCCCGGGGCCAUGCGACCGACGCUGCUGUGGUCGCUGCUGCUGCUGCUCGGAGUCUUCGCCGCCGCCGCCGCGGCCCCGCCAGCACAGCUAACUUUGGAGACCUACCAAGAAUGGUGCAAUGAUUCAGCAGCUACUCAUGACCCUCUUUCCCAGCUGCCCGCUCCUCAGCACCCGAAGAUUCGCCUGUACAACGCAGAGCAGGUCCUGAGUUGGGAGCCAGUGGCCCUGAGCAAUAGCACGAGGCCUGUUGUCUACCAAGUGCAGUUUAAAUACACCGACAGUAAAUGGUUCACGGCCGACAUCAUGUCCAUAGGGGUGAAUUGUACACAGAUCACAGCAACAGAGUGUGACUUCACUGCCGCCAGUCCCUCAGCAGGCUUCCCAAUGGAUUUCAAUGUCACUCUACGCCUUCGAGCUGAGCUGGGAGCACUCCAUUCUGCCUGGGUGACAAUGCCUUGGUUUCAACACUAUCGGAAUGUGACUGUCGGGCCUCCAGAAAACAUUGAGGUGACCCCAGGAGAAGGCUCCCUCAUCAUCAGGUUCUCCUCUCCCUUUGACAUCGCUGAUACCUCCACGGCCUUUUUUUGUUAUUAUGUCCAUUACUGGGAAAAAGGAGGAAUCCAACAGGUCAAAGGCCCUUUCAGAAGCAACUCCAUUUCAUUGGAUAACUUAAAACCCUCCAGAGUGUACUGUUUACAAGUCCAGGCACAACUGCUUUGGAACAAAAGUAACAUCUUUAGAGUCGGGCAUUUAAGCAACAUAUCUUGCUACGAAACAAUGGCAGAUGCCUCCACUGAGCUUCAGCAAGUCAUCCUGAUCUCCGUGGGAACAUUUUCGUUGCUGUCGGUGCUGGCAGGAGCCUGUUUCUUCCUGGUCCUGAAAUAUAGAGGCCUGAUUAAAUACUGGUUUCACACUCCACCAAGCAUCCCAUUACAGAUAGAAGAGUAUUUAAAAGACCCAACUCAGCCCAUCUUAGAGGCCUUGGACAAGGACAGCUCACCAAAGGAUGACGUCUGGGACUCUGUGUCCAUUAUCUCGUUUCCGGAAAAGGAGCAAGAAGAUGUUCUCCAAACGCUUUGAACCAAAGCAUGGGCCUAGCCCACUGGCUCCCUGGAAGAGAUCAAGCCAUCGGAGCUGCUAGAGUUCUGUCUGGACUUUCCAGAGACCAGUAUUCCCUUUUGCUGCCUCUAAAAGGCCUGUCCCUGCAGACAUGAGAGACAGCAGGUCUCAUGGGGGUGACAAGCUUUUUUUUUUUUUCUUAAAGAAUUUUCAAAAUCAAAUUCCAGAAUGAUUUUACGGAGAUAUCCCAGGAAAAUUAAGGCUUCUCUUAAACACUAAAAAGGCAUGUAAUUGCUUGUUAGCAAAAUGGAUAUGACACAUCUCUGAUACUUUUUUCAUUAUUGGUUGGGCUGAGCAGUCAGAAGACCUGGUCGUCGUCUUGACUUUGGCAAAUGAGCCGGAGCCCCUUGGGCAGGUCACACAACCUGUCCCAGCGAGGGACACCGAGUGGCCCUUCAUGUACAUCCAUGGUGUGCUGGCUUAAAAUGUAAUUAAUCUUGUAAAUAUACUCCUAGUAAUUUAAGAUUUUGUUUUUAAACUGGAAAUAAAAGAUUGUAUAGUGCAUGUUUUUUAAA